GUCACACUGCUCGUGUUACAAGAAAACCAGCCAGGGUUCUGCUUUUCUGCUCUGCCGCAGCCUUUAACACCUGCCAGGGUUCUGUCCGAGUGUAUGGGUUUCGUAGUCCUCCUCUCCAAGGCGUUGACUGAGCACAGAGCACCGGCCGCCGCCACAUCCCACUCUGGCGCGGGGUCUGCGGAGCCACAAAUCCAGCCAGGAACCGAGUGCCGCCCGAUCCGAGCAUCCGUCGCAUUUUGACCUGGGGUUCCCGGGUCUCAAGGCCCACUUUCUGGGGCAGGCAGUGGGGAGAGAAGCCCAAGCUGGGGUAUGGGCAGUUGCAGUGCGGUGGAAGGGGAAAGCUCGGGCGAGAGCUUGGCUGGACCCUCAGAGGAGGGGUCCGGGGAAGGCGGGACCGCAGGCUCCGGGAAAGGAGAGAGAGAUAGGGACGGAGGAGGGGCGGAGGGGGAGUAAGAAAGAACUAAGAACCACUCGAAAGCAAUCAGAAAACUUGGCGUUUCCAGACAUUUUUUUUUUUUUUUGUAGGGGGAACAGGCUCUCACUCUGUCGCCCAAGCUGGAGUGCAGUGGUGCGAUCUCGACUCACUUUACCCUGGACUUCCUCGGGCUCAAGUGAUCCUCCAGCCUCAGCCUCCCGGGCAUCUGAGACUACAUUUGAGUCUACAGGCGCGCGCCACUAAGCCUGAGUCUUUCAGGACUGAUUUUGGUGGAAGAAGACAGCAGGCGGUGGGCAUUCACUGUGCUGGUGGGAAGUCUGGUUACAUUAAGAAAGGAAUUCUAGCAAAGUUAUUCUGUAAAUACAACAGAAUCAGUUGCUUUUGUUAAAUAUAUUGGUAAGCUUCCUGAUUUUUUUCACCUGAAUUCUCAAUUUGUUAUUGAAUAGUUCAGUUUUAUUUAGGGUUUCAAUUUUAUUUAGGAAACAAUAUCUCUACCUUACAAAGAAUCUGCAAGUAGCACUGACUAUAAUACCUUUAUACCCAAAGGAAGAGCUGGGAUAGAGCUCCCUAAGACUUUUCUGCCUGCAAAAGAUAUGGGUGGGGUUGCCAUUUGAAUACAGUUACCAAUGAAAAACUAUCAGCUUAUCUAGGCUUUAACAAUAAAGUUCAUGGGGGUAAAGAGAAAAGAUUUAACUUUGAAGUCCCCAUAUAUCAAAAAGAAUAUUUUACAGGUAACUUGACAAAGAUGUUUCAGUGGUCUCGGAAUGCAAGACAGAAUCCUGACGGUAGAAAUUUCUAGGCAAGGGUCUAAAUUAGGCAAACUGGUAAGAUUGUGAAUGUCCCAGCCUUUAUUUCUGAAUCUUGACCUCUGAACUCUGCUGCCUCUCUCUAAACAUGUUUCUGCCUACAGGUACUUCAGGACUGAUUUUGGUGUAAGAAGACAGCAGGUGUACACUUGAUGAUGCUACUUCCUUACCUCUCAUUCAUUCCUCAACCCAUUGUAAAAUAAUGUCAAUUAAUAUAGGUUCCUUUGCUGAACACCUGUGAACCAAAGCAUAGUUUUAAAUGCUUGUUGUAAACUAUCUGAGUUAAUCUUCAUAAUAACAGUCACAGGUGGCUGCACCAUGUUUUAUAGUAAGAAAAUAGAGUUAGAAAGAGUAAAUAUCUAGACUAAUAUAACAGUACUAAAUGGCAGAACUGGAAUUCAAGCCAUCUUCAUUGACUCUGUUCUCCAAGACCUUAGCCCCUGGUUUAUUGCCUCCUGAUGCCCAUUUCCCAGGUGUCUGAAGAGCAUUUUUCAAAGUCACAGUUAACCUUAAUUUUACUAAACUUAGGUUUAGUAACACUUUCCAGUCAUUACCUAGCUGUAUCUGUCAGCAGUAUUAGACAUCUUAAAACCUUGGCAGGUGACUUUGUUCCAGGCUUUGUUAAUACCAAAUACCCUUGAUUUUUCUCUUACUUCUUUGAUUUUUCAUACUCAGACUUUUCUACAGUCUCCUUUUCAAUGUGGUCUUCUUUUACUUAUCUUCUAAAGUUGAUGUUCAUGGAGAAUCUGUUCCAAACCUAGAUGUUCUCAUGCCAUGGUACACAUGCCCCUCAGCUGAUCCACUACUUCUGUGUUUCAAUGCUAAUGAUUUCACCUGGCCAGUUCUAGUGCAUCUUUUAAGUCUUGGCCUAAAUGGAACCUACUCCUGGAAGUCUUAUGGAACCAUGGUCUCCAGAUUCGUUCAGAUACCCUAUUCAAUGUGUUUUCCCUCUUAGAGCCCAUGUCACAGAUGAUGGUAAAGGCUAAUUUCAUUAGUUCCCUUCCCUGCCAGCCAGUCAGCUCCUAAAGAGACUAUACCUGUCUUUCUUGCUAUUGUCUUAUCCCAGCACAUAUUAGACACGUUUUAAAUAUUUUCUAAUAAAUGAAUUGCAGGCCUGUAACAAUUUUUUAAUCAAAAAUGAAACAAAUAUUCUAAUACUUUAAGGUGCAAGUUCAACAUGGAGGCAAAUCACUGCUCCCUGGGUGUGUAUCCAUCUUACCCAGACCUGGUCAUCGAUGUCGGAGAAGUGACUCUGGGAGAAGAAAACAGAAAAAAGCUACAGAAAACUCAGAGAGACCAAGAGAGGGCGAGAGUUAUACGGGCCGCGUGUGCUUUAUUAAACUCAGGAGGAGGAGUGAUUCAGAUGGAAAUGGCCAACAGGGAUGAGCGUCCCACAGAGAUGGGACUGGAUUUAGAAGAAUCCUUGAGAAAGCUUAUUCAGUAUCCAUAUUUGCAGGCUUUCUUUGAGACUAAGCAACACGGAAGGUGUUUUUAUAUUUUUGUUAAAUCUUGGAGUGGUGAUCCUUUCCUUAAAGAUGGUUCUUUCAAUUCCCGCAUUUGCAGCCUUAGUUCUUCAUUAUACUGUAGAUCUGGCACCUCUGUGCUUCACAUGAAUUCAAGACAGGCAUUCGAUUUCCUGAAGACCAAGGAAAGACAGUCCAAAUAUAAUCUGAUUAAUGAAGGGUCUCCACCUAGUAAAAUUAUGAAAGCUGUAUACCAGAACAUAUCUGAGUCAAAUCCUGCAUAUGAAGUUUUCCAAACUGACACUAUUGAAUAUGGUGAAAUCCUAUCUUUUCCUGAGUCUCCAUCCAUAGAGUUUAAACAGUUCUCUACAAAACAUAUCCAACAAUAUGUAGAAAAUAUAAUUCCAGAGUACAUCUCUGCAUUUGCAAACACUGAGGGAGGCUAUCUUUUUAUUGGAGUGGAUGAUAAGAGUAGGAAAGUCCUGGGAUGUGCCAAAGAACAGGUUGACCCUGACUCUUUGAAAAAUGUAAUUGCAAGAGCAAUUUCUAAGUUGCCCAUUGUUCAUUUUUGCUCUUCAAAACCUCGGGUAGAGUACAGCACCAAAAUCGUAGAAGUGUUUUGUGGGAAAGAGUUGUAUGGCUAUCUCUGUGUGAUUAAAGUGAAGGCAUUCUGUUGUGUGGUGUUCUCGGAAGCUCCCAAGUCAUGGAUGGUGAGGGAGAAGUACAUCCGCCCCUUGACAACUGAGGAAUGGGUAGAGAAAAUGAUGGACGCAGAUCCAGAGUUUCCUCCAGACUUUGCUGAGGCCUUUGAGUCUCAGUUGAGUCUAUCUGACAGUCCUUCACUUUGCAGACCAGUGUAUUCUAAGAAAGGUCUGGAACACAAAGCUGAUCUACAACAACAUUUAUUUCCAGUUCCACCAGGACAUUUGGAAUGUACUCCAGAGUCCCUCUGGAAGGAGCUGUCUUUACAGCAUGAAGGACUAAAGGAGUUAAUACACAAGCAAAUGCGACCUUUCUCCCAGGGAAUUGUGAUCCUCUCUAGAAGCUGGGCUGUGGACCUGAACUUGCAGGAGAAGCCAGGAGUCAUCUGUGAUGCUCUGCUGAUAGCACAGAACAGCACCCCCAUUCUCUACACCAUUCUCAGGGAGCAGGAUGCAGAGGGCCAGGACUACUGCACUCGCACCGCCUUUACUUUGAAGCAGAAGCUAGUGAACAUGGGGGGCUACACCGGGAAGGUGUGUGUCAGGGCCAAGGUCCUCUGCCUGAGUCCUGAGAGCAGCGCAGAGGCCUUGGAGGCUGCAGUGUCUCCGAUGGAUUACCCUGCGUCCUAUAGCCUUGCAGGCACCCAGCACAUGGAAGCCCUGCUGCAGUCCCUCGUGAUUGUCUUACUCGGCUUCAGGUCUCUCUUGAGUGACCAGCUCGGCUGUGAGGUUUUAAAUCUGCUCACAGCCCAGCAGUAUGAGAUAUUCUCCAGAAGCCUCCGCAAGAACAGAGAGUUGUUUGUCCACGGCUUACCUGGCUCAGGGAAGACCAUCAUGGCCAUGAAGAUCAUGGAGAAGAUCAGGAAUGUGUUUCACUGUGAGGCACACAGAAUUCUCUACGUUUGUGAAAACCAGCCUCUGAGGAACUUUAUCAGUGAUAGAAAUAUCUGCCGAGCAGAGACCCGGGAAACUUUCCUAAGAGAAAAAUUUGAACACAUUCAACACAUCGUCAUUGACGAAGCUCAGAAUUUCCGUACUGAAGAUGGGGACUGGUAUAGGAAGGCAAAAACCAUCACUCAGAGAGAAAAGGAUUGUCCAGGAGUUCUCUGGAUCUUUCUGGACUACUUUCAGACCAGUCACUUGGGUCACAGUGGCCUUCCCCCUCUCUCAGCACAGUAUCCAAGAGAAGAGCUCACCAGAGUAGUUCGCAAUGCAGAUGAAAUAGCCGAGUACAUACAACAAGAAAUGCAACUAAUUAUAGAAAAUCCUCCAAUUAAUAUCCCCCAUGGGUAUCUGGCAAUUCUCAGUGAAGCUAAAUGGGUUCCAGGUGUUCCAGGCAACACAAAGAUUAUUAAAAACUUUACUUUGGAGCAAAUAGUGACCUAUGUGGCAGACACCUGCAGGUGCUUCUUUGAAAGGGGCUAUUCUCCAAAGGAUGUUGCUGUGCUUGUCAGCACCGUGACAGAAGUGGAGCAGUAUCAGUCUAAGCUCUUGAAAGCAAUGAGGAAGAAAAUGGUGGUGCAGCUCAGUGAUGCAUGUGAUAUGUUGGGUGUGCACAUUGUGUUGGACAGUGUCCGGCGAUUCUCAGGCCUGGAAAGGAGCAUAGUGUUUGGGAUCCAUCCAAGGACAGCUGACCCAGCUAUCUUACCCAAUAUUCUGAUCUGUCUGGCUUCCAGGGCAAAACAGCACCUAUAUAUUUUUCUGUGAAGUGACUAUUAGGAAGAACUCCAAACCAAAAUACUGUGUAAAUGUCUAUGGGUGACAGUCUGCUGAUGGUAGAAACCUUUCUUUUUAGUUCACAAGUCAGUUAGAGAUUUGGACAGAGCUGACACAAAGAGUUUGGAGCUCCCCCAUUUCUGGCUCUCCUUUCAGGGGUUCCUCCCCCAACUCUUUUCAGCAGUGGUGGCUGCCCCCCAUUCUGACCCCUGACUCUUGCAGCCAGAAAGAUGGUGGUUUUCUAAAGGAACUUUAGCUGUGCUGCACAAUGCAGACCUGUGUCUUGCUCUCUGGGUAAAAGCCAUAAAAAUAAGAAACUCAGCCUGUGGCCUUUCUUCCAAGGCUGGAGUUCUCGAGUUCUUUUAUGUGACUUCGUGUAGUUUGUUGCUUUAAAAAAUUUGUCCAGAAUUGUUUUCUGCAGAAGCAUGGUCUGUUAGGAGCUUACAGGCCAUAGGAGAAGCAGUUGUUUCCUGAAUUUAUCUUUGCUGUAUUCAUUUAGGGCUUGGGAGAGUCCCAAGAUAAUUCAGUCACUGUCAGAUUAAUCAUUUCGGCAGAACAAACAAUAUUGUUAUGAUUAUUUAAUCCUUAAAAUUGUGAUCUCCAGAGUUUGUUAUCAGAAUAACCCAGACCAAGGCUUAAUUGUAAUAGUGAACAUUAAUGGUACCUUUACAGAGAAAUUAUAGGCCAAGAGAAAAUGCUGGCUUUCAGUAGAAGUUAAUAUUAGAAACCCAAAUCUGGUUCUGAAAGUGUGUAUCAGAUGUACGGUGAACAAACUUGGGAAAGAUUUUCUUUAAAAAUCAAUGAGCGUUGGCCAGGCACGGUGGCUCACACCUGUAAUCCCAGCUGUUUGGGAGGCUGAGGCAGGUGGAUCACCUGAGGUCAGGAGUUCAAGACCAGCCUGGCCAACAUGGAGAAACCCCAUCUCUACUAAAAAUACAAAAAUUAGCAGGGCAUGGUGGUGCAUGCCUGUAUCCCAGCUACUUGGGAGGCUGAAGCAUGAGAAUCACUUGAAUCCUGGAGGCAGAGGUUGCAGUGAGCUGAGAUCAUGUCACUGUACUCCAGCCUGGGCAACAGAGUGAGACUGUCUCAAAAAGAAGAAGAAGAAAAAAAAUGCAGUGAGUUUAUGUUGUUACAUUGUAACAUCUCAGCGUAGCUGUAUGCAUUACUCUAUAGCAUAACUACUUAAGUUUUAUGUCAUUCUUGAACUGUGAUUUUUUUUUCUAUUUGCUUUCAUAGUUUGGUGGGCCAUUGUUAUGGACUGAAUGUUUGUGUCCCAUCCUCACCCCUAAAUUCCCAUGUUGAAGCCCCAACCUUCACUGUGGAGCUGGGGCUGCUAAGGAAGUAAUUAAGGUUACACGAAGUCACAGUGGAGAAUCUGAUCUGCUAAGACUGGUGUCCUUAUAGGGAGAGACCCCAGAGAGCUUGUUCCCUUCCUCCCUGUGCACACAAACAAGAGGGCAUGGGAGCACACAGAGAGAUGGCAGCCACCUACAAGCCAAGAGGAGAAGCCUCACAAUGAACCCCCCCCCCCACCCUGCUGGCACCUAUGUCUUCGACUUCCAGCCCCCAGACUGUGAGAAAUAAAUUUCUGUUGGUUCAGCCAUCCAGUCUCUAGUGUUUUGUUAUUGCAGCCUGAGAACACAGCUGUAUGAUCAUUCAUCAAACUAAAAACACUGAUACUUAACAAUGCUAAUGCAAUUACUUAUUUGCUUUUCAGUCUCUACAAAACAUUCUAAAACACUAAUCUAAAUACUAACAAUAAAAUAUUUGCAUAACUAAUGAAAAUUAAGAAACCACAUGCCCAAUAUUCCAUUUAUAAGUAAUCCUAUUUGGCUGAUUUCCCUCCAUAUUGUAAGUUUUGAACUUUUCUGCCAGUCUUUCUCCUAUUUGUGUUAACUCAUGGAAUUCCAGUUGUCUAGCCUUGAAAUUGUAGGCUCUUCUAACUUGAGCAAAAUCUGACAGAUCAGCAAAAUAAGGAGAAAAAUAUUUCUUCUUUCUUUCUGGCUGCAUUAAAUGAGAUACAGCUCAGCACCAAAAAGCUAUCUUUGUAAAUGUUCUUAGUAAACUCCCUGGUCUUUGGAGUUAUUUCAGCCUUUGAGAGUAAUUCUUUAAAAGUCUAAUUCUGACUGGUUGAAUCUCUCUAUAUGAUUUAUUGCCCUAGUAAUAUUUGAAACAGUAUCAUAUUUUAAAAUAUAUAAAUAUUUAUGAAUUUUUGUUCAGCCCAAAGAGGAUUACUGAUGCUUUCUUCUUUUUCCAUAUGAUGAGGAAAUGUUUAGCUUAUAUAUUUAUUGCAUUUCUGUUUUAAAUAAAAAAUUGAGAGUUUGUGUUUCAUUAAACUGAAAAAAAAGGUUCUGUAAAAUAAAUGAUUAAAUGGAGGAAAAGGAGAAGACUGAGGCCAGCAACUCCAUGAUACAGCCAAAAAUGAGCCAGUAAAAGAUUAAGCAAGAUUAACUGUAAAUUUUUUUUUUUUUUUUUUUUAAAGAGAAAAGGUCUCACUGUGUUUCCCAGGCUGGAGGGUAGUGGUGUGAUCAUAGUUCACUAGAGCCCUGAACUCCUGGGCUCAAGUGAUCCUCUUGCCUUAGCCUCCCAUUGCUGGGAUUAUAGGCAUGAGCCACUGUGUCAGGCUUAAUUGGGUUUUGAUGGGUACCUGCCUAUCUCUGUAAUUUGGCUCUAGUCAUAUAGGACCUGCUUCAUUAAAGAUCUGAAAAUCUAUCCAGCCAUUGUAAAAUGAAACAAAAUGUUUUGAAAAUUUAAAUUAGCCUUUUAUUUUAGUUCAGACAUAUAGAAAAGUUGCAAGCAUAGUACAGAAAGUUCCUAUAUACCCCACUUAGUGCCCUCCUUUUUAAAAUUUUUUUAAACCUAGCUUAUUUCCUUUAAGAUUUCUGAGAAUUCCAGGAAUGCUCACAGAUCUGUCCUUGUAGUCUCCUGCCACUUCUUGCUAUGGAGUGCUGUACCAAGGUCUCUGCUAGUUUCUAGUUGGCUUGACAUAAUGACUUUCCUAAACUUCUUCUGCUCUGAAUCUCAAGCAUGGAAAGCGGUCACAUCUUUUGUUUCACGAAUUAACAGUCAACACCUGGCCCUACUUUUAACAAAACUUAGUAAAGCCUUGAGCAUAGUGAAAGACAAAUAUUUAAAUUAUAUAUUAGCAGGAGGCUGAGGUGGGAGGAUCAUAUGAGGCCAGCCUGGGCAGCAUAGCAUGACCCCCCCCUCGAGAAGACAACAAAAAAUUAUCUGGGUGUGGUGGUGUGCUCCUGCAGUCCUAGCUAUUCCAGAGGCCGAGGCGAGAGGAUCGCUUGAUUCCAGGAGUUCAAGGCUGUAGUUAGCGAUAAUCGUGUCACUGAAUCCUAGCCUGGGCAACAGAAUAAGACCCCAUGUCUAACAAAAUAAUAAUAAAACAAUCAAAAGUUUAAAAUUAGUUAUUAAAUGUCAGUGUGCCCAGAGUCCUUUGACCACAGAUGAUCCUGAUGGCCUUCUCUCGCCUUGUCCCUGUGCCUCCUUCUACCAUUUUUCUUCCUGAGAUUCAAAAGUAAGUAGCGGACAGGGUUCCCAUUUACCACUAAAUACUUCAGUGGGUGUUUCCUAAAAGGACAUUUAUAGUACCAUCAUCAAAAUCAGUAAAUUAACCCUGAUACUAUUAUCUAAUCUGUAGACUUUAUUGAAUUAUAUCAGUUGUGCCUCAAGUGUCUUUAUGUUUUUUUCUCAAAAGAGAAAAAGUUCUGGUCCAGGAUUUGAUCUAAGAUCAUGCAUUGUAUUGAGCUUUCCUUUCUUUUAAGUCUCAUUUAAUCUGGAGAUGUUAAUCUGUCUUUGUCAUAUCUUUGACACUAUUGAAGAGGACUGGCCUAUUAUUUUGCAGAGUAUCUGAUUUUGGGUCAUUUCAUGUGUUCUCAUGAUUAGAUUCAGGUUAUGCAUUUUUGGCAUGAAUUCCAUAGAAGGGCUGUUACGGUUCUCAGUUCACGGUAUUAGAAGGCACUUGAUAGUGAUUAGUUCCAUUCCUGAUGAUGUUAACUCUGAUCAUUUGGAUAAAGUGGCGUCUGCCAGGUUUCCCUACUGUGCAGUUACAAUUUGCUUUUUGUAAUUAAUAAAGUGUGUGUGUGUGUGUGUGUGGAGGGGGGGUGUUUUUGCUUCUGAACGCAUAAUAUUUGAGAUUUUUUUCUAAUUAAAAAGUAAUUAUUCAAAGAGUUCAGAGAACUGAUACUGAUCACAUUCUUUGACCCCACAUGCAAAUACAUUAUAAACUAGUAAUAAAACGGUAACUAGAAAAAUGUUCAUAUCUUUUGGAAUUAAAAAAGUGUUUAACUCGUGGAUCAAAGCAGAAAUUCUGUAACCAUUGUCACAGCAGGUUCUAACAAGCAAGUUUAAGGAGGAGAGAAUUUCAGUCCUAGAGAAUUUCAGUCUUAUUCAAAUGCUUUCCUAGAAAGAGGAAACAGUUCCUAACUAAUUUCAUGAGGCUGGCAUAAUCUUGAUAACAAGUCUGAUAGGUAAAGUAUGAAAGGAAAAUUGCAGGUCACUCAAUUAUCACUCAAAUAUCUACAUGAAAAAUUCUAAACAAAAUUUUAGCAAACAAAAUCCAACAAUUUGUAAAAGUGAUAAUACACCACGACCAAGGUGGUUCAAGUCAGGAAUUCAACGUUGAUUUUGGCGUUAAAAAAUCAAUCAUCAGGCCCAGUGAGGUGGCUCACUCCUGUAAUCCCAGACUUUCUGGAGGCUGAAGGAGGAAAGAUCCUUCAGGCCAGAAGUUUGAGUCUGCACUGAGCUGUGACUGCAUCACCGCACUCUAGCCUGGGUGCCAGUUUGAGACCCUGUCUCCAAGAAAAAAAAAUUAAUCAGUGUAAUUCACCACAGAUUAAGAGUUCAAAAGAGAAAAAUCACAUGAUCAUCUGAAUAGAGGAAAAAGCUUUUGAUAAAGUUCAACAUCCAUUCAUAAUAAGGACUCUCAGCAACUUAGAAGUAUAAAAACACUUUUGGAAAUCAACAAAGGGAAUUUACAGCAUGAACAAACAGCAAGCCAGCAUGGUGGCUCACACCUGUAAUCUCAGCACUUCCAGAGGCCAAGGCAGGAGAAUCACUUGAGCCCAGGGGUUAGAGACAAGCCUUGGCAACAUAGCAAGAUCCUGGCUCUACAAAAAAUAAAAUAAAAUGAAAUAAAAUUUAAAAAUUAGCUGGGUUUGGUGGUGUGUGCCUGUAGUCCCAGCUACUGGGAGGCUGAGGUGAGAGGAUCACUGGAGCCCAGGAGGUGAAGGCUGCAGUGGGCUAAAAACAACCAGAACAACCCCCCAACCCCCUCCCCGCAAAACACUAUAAAGAAUAGCAACACAAGGUUCAAUGUAAACUUUGAUAUGGUGUUUUACCUCUGAGGAGAGGCUUAUUGUUAAUAUUCUUUAGCCGUGUAAGGGGUUCACAGAUGUUCAUACUUUUGUUCUUUAUACCUUAUAUGUAUUCUAUAAAUAUUGUUUCUACUCAAUAGUUAAUAAAAACAUAAUUUAAAAGUUC